ACUCCAGCUCUGGCUUCUGGGCUCCGAGGAGGGGUGGGGACGGUGGGGACGGUGGGGACAUCAGGCUGCCCCGCAGUACCAGGGAGCGACUGAAGUGCCCAUGCCGCUUGCUCCGGAGAAGCCCAGGUGUGGCCUCACUCACAUCCCACUCUGAGUCCAAAUGUUCUCUCCCUGGAAGAUAUCAAUGUUUCUGUCUGUUCGUGAGGACUCCGUGCCCACCACGGCCUCUUUCAGCGCCGACAUGCUCAAUGUCACCUUGCAAGGGCCCACUCUUAACGGGACCUUUGCCCAGAGCAAAUGCCCCCAAGUGGAGUGGCUGGGCUGGCUCAACACCAUCCAGCCCCCCUUCCUCUGGGUGCUGUUCGUGCUGGCCACCCUAGAGAACAUCUUUGUCCUCAGCGUCUUCUGCCUGCACAAGAGCAGCUGCACGGUGGCAGAGAUCUACCUGGGGAACCUGGCCGCAGCAGACCUGAUCCUGGCCUGCGGGCUGCCCUUCUGGGCCAUCACCAUCUCCAACAACUUCGACUGGCUCUUUGGGGAGACGCUCUGCCGCGUGGUGAAUGCCAUUAUCUCCAUGAACCUGUACAGCAGCAUCUGUUUCCUGAUGCUGGUGAGCAUCGACCGCUACCUGGCCCUGGUGAAAACCAUGUCCAUGGGCCGGAUGCGCGGCGUGCGCUGGGCCAAGCUCUACAGCUUGGUGAUCUGGGGGUGUACGCUGCUCCUGAGCUCACCCAUGCUGGUGUUCCGGACCAUGAAGGAGUACAGCGAUGAGGGCCACAACGUCACCGCUUGUGUCAUCAGCUACCCAUCCCUCAUCUGGGAAGUGUUCACCAACAUGCUCCUGAAUGUCGUGGGCUUCCUGCUGCCCCUGAGUGUCAUCACCUUCUGCACGAUGCAGAUCAUGCAGGUGCUGCGGAACAACGAGAUGCAGAAGUUCAAGGAGAUCCAGACAGAGAGGAGGGCCACGGUGCUAGUCCUGGUUGUGCUGCUGCUAUUCAUCAUCUGCUGGCUGCCCUUCCAGAUCAGCACCUUCCUGGAUACGCUGCAUCGCCUCGGCAUCCUCUCCAGCUGCCAGGACGAGCGCAUCAUCGAUGUAAUCACACAGAUCGCCUCCUUCAUGGCCUACAGCAACAGCUGCCUCAACCCACUGGUGUACGUGAUCGUGGGCAAGCGCUUCCGAAAGAAGUCUUGGGAGGUGUACCAGGGAGUGUGCCAGAAAGGGGGCUGCAGGUCAGAACCCAUUCAGAUGGAGAACUCCAUGGGCACACUGCGGACCUCCAUCUCCGUGGAACGCCAGAUUCACAAACUGCAGGACUGGGCAGGGAGCAGACAGUGAGCAAACGCCAGCAGGGCUGCUGUGAAUUUGUGUAAGGAUUGAGGGACAGUUGCUUUUCAGCAUGGGCCCAGGAAUGCCAAGGAGACAUCUAUGCACGACCUUGGGAAAUGAGUUGAUGUCUCCGGUAAAACACCGGAGACUAAUUCCUGCCCUGCCCAAUUUUGCAGGGAGCAUGGCUGUGAGGAUGGGGUGAACUCACGCACAGCCAAGGACUCCAAAAUCACAACAGCAUUACUGUUCUUAUUUGCUGCCACACCUGAGCCAGCCUGCUCCUUCCCAGGAGUGGAGGAGGCCUGGGGGCAGGGAGAGGAGUGACUGAGCUUCCCUCCCGUGUGUUCUCCGUCCCUGCCCCAGCAAGACAACUUAGAUCUCCAGGAGAACUGCCAUCCAGCUUUGGUGCAAUGGCUGAGUGCACAAGUGAGUUGUUGCCCUGGGUUUCUUUAAUCUAUUCAGCUAGAACUUUGAAGGACAAUUUCUUGCAUUAAUAAAGGUUAAGCCCUGAGGGGUCCCUGAUAACAACCUGGAGACCAGGAUUUUAUGGCUCCCCUCACUGAUGGACAAGGAGGUCUGUGCCAAAGAAGAAUCCAAUAAGCACAUAUUGAGCACUUGCUGUAUAUGCAGUAUUGAGCACUGUAGGCAAGAGGGAAGAAAGAGAAGGAGCCAUCUCCAUCUUGAAGGAACUCAAAGACUCAAGUGGGAACGACUGGGCACUGCCACCACCAGAAAGCUGUUCGACGAGACGGUCGAGCAGGGUGCUGUGGGUGAUAUGGACAGCAGAAGGGGGAGACCAAGGUUCCAGCUCAACCAAUAACUAUUGCACAACCAUCUGUCCCUGCCUCAGUUCCCUCUUCUGUAACAUGAAGUCGUUGUGAGGGUUAAAGGCAGUAACAGGUAUAAAGUACUUAGAAAAGCAAAGGGUGCUACGUACAUGUGAGGCAUCAUUACGCAGACGUAACUGGGAUAUGUUUACUAUAAGGAAAAGACACUGAGGUCUAGAAAUAGCUCCGUGGAGCAGAAUCAGUAUUGGGAGCCGGUGGCGGUGUGAAGCACCAGUGUCUGGCACACAGUAGGUGCUCAUUGGCUCCCUUCCACCUGUCAUUCCCACCACCCUGAGGCCCCAACCGCCACACACACAGGAGCAUUUGGAGAGAAGGCCAUGUCUUCAAAGUCUGAUUUGUGAUGAGGCAGAGGAAGAUAUUUCUAAUCGGUCUUGCCCAGAGGAUCACAGUGCUGAGACCCCCCACCACCAGCCGGUACCUGGGAAGGGGGAGAGUGCAGGCCUGCUCAGGGACUGUUCCUGUCUCAGCAACCAAGGGAUUGUUCCUGUCAAUCAAUGGUUUAUUGGAAGGUGGCCCAGUAUGAGCCCUAGAAGAGUGUGAAAAGGAAUGGCAAUGGUGUUCACCAUCGGCAGUGCCAGGGCAGCACUCAUUCACUUGAUAAAUGAAUAUUUAUUAGCUGGUUGGAGAGCUAGAACCUGGAGAGCUAGAACCUGGAGAACUAGAACCUGGAGGGCUAGAACUGGAGAGGCUAGAACCAAGAAGGGCUAGAACCUGGAGGGGCUAGAACCUAGAGAAGCUAAAACCUGAGCUAGAAGCUGGAGGACUAGAACCUGGAGGGCUGGAAUCUGGAGAGCUAGAACCUGGAGGGCUAGAACCUGGAGGGCUAGAAUCUGGAGAGCUAGAACCUGGAGGGCUAGAAUCUGGAGAGCUAGAACCUGGAGGGCUAGAACCUGGAGAGCUAGAACCUAGAAGGGCUAGAACCUGGAGGGCUGGAAUCUGGAGAGCUAGAACCUGGAGGGCUAGAACCUGGAGGGCUAGAACCUAGAAGGGCUAGAACCUGGAGGGCUGGAAUCUGGAGAGCUAGAACCUGGAGGGCUAGAACCUGGAGGGCUAGAACCUAGAAGGGCUAGAACCUGGAGGGCUAGAACCUGGCAGGUUAGAACCUAGAAGGGCUAGAACCUGGAGAGCCAGAACCUGGAGGGCUAGAACCUGGAAGGGCUAGAACCUGUAGAGCUAGAACAUGGAGAGCUAGAACCCGGCAGGCUAGAACCUGGCAAGCUAGAACCUGGAGGGAAUGAACCUGGAGGGCUAGAACCUGGAGAAUGAGAAAAAUUUACAUGGCAAAGAGCCCAUAAAUCCUGACCAAUCCAACUCUGAAUUUUAAAGCAAAAGCGUCAAAAAAAAGAUUCCCUCCUUACCCCCAACCCACUCUUUUUUCCCACCACCCACUCUCCUCUGCCUCAGUAAGUAUCUGGAGGAAGAAAACAGGUGAAAGAAGAAGUAAAAACCAUUUAGUAUUAGUAUUAGAAUGAAGUCAAACUGUGCCACACAUGGUGAAUGAAAAAAAAAAAAAGAGGCUGUGUUUUGUCACACAGGGCAGUCAUUCAGCACCAGAGCACGUGAUGGUCUGAGACUCUCUUAGGAGCAGAGCUCUGCCGCAAUGGCCAUGUGGGGAUCCACACCUGGUCUGAGGGGCAACUGAGUCUGCGGGAGAAGAGCGGCCCUAUGCAUGGUGUAGAUGCCCUGAUAAAGAACAUCUGUCCUGUGAAAGACUCAAUGAGCUGUUAUGUUGUAAACAGGAAGCAUUUCACAUCCAAACGAGAAAAUCAUGUAAACAUGUGUCUUUUCUGUAGAGCAUAAUAAAUGGAUGAGGUUUUUGCA